AGCUUGCCCCUGGGGAGGCUCCAGACAGCUUUGUUCCUGGGCAGUGGCGGGGCUGGCCGAGGCUGCGGCGUUUCUCCCCAAGGAAGUGUCUUCUCCGCUUUCCCUGUUCUUCUGUUUCUCACACACUUUCUAUCUCAUUCUGUAACUUUCAAGCCUUUCCUUCUAACUGUAUGUAUUUAGUUACUUGUUUUCAAGCUGGUUCCCUCUCUGGCCCCCUGGCCUGGGGAAAGCCUCCACACUUACUGCGGGUCUUGUUUAGAGUCUGAGUUUGUGAGAUUAUUUGGGGGAGAGUGGGCGAGUGGCUGACAGGUGACCCCCAGGAGGAGGAUUCCUGGGGCUGGUGUCUUCUCCCAGCUGCUGCUUCCAGUGGGCCUGGGCCCAGGACUGGACCUCCGCUGGCACCCCUGAGUGCCUCCCUGCCAGGCCAUGCUGCUGUAGACCCUAACAGCGUCUCUUCCUGGCCAAGAGAAGCCUGUCCCCAAGAACAGGAGAGCCAUGGCCGGCCUCCGAGGGAACGCUGUGGCUGGCCUCCUCUGGAUGCUGCUGCUGUGGAGUGGGGGCGGCGGCUGCCAGGCUCAGCGGGCAGGUUGCAAAAGUGUCCACUACGAUCUGGUCUUCCUCCUGGACACCUCCUCCAGCGUGGGCAAGGAGGACUUUGAGAAGGUCCGGCAGUGGGUGGCCAACCUGGUGGACACCUUCGAGGUGGGCCCCGACCGCACCCGUGUGGGGGUCGUGCGCUACAGCGACCGGCCCACCACGGCCUUCGAGUUGGGACUCUUUGGCUCGCAGGAGGAGGUCAAGGCGGCUGCCCGGCGUCUCGCCUACCACGGGGGCAACACCAACACGGGAGACGCGCUCCGCUACAUCACGGCCCGCAGCUUCUCCCCACACGCCGGCGGCCGCCCCAGGGACCGCGCCUACAAGCAGGUGGCCAUCCUGCUCACCGACGGCCGCAGCCAGGACCUGGUGCUGGACGCCGCGGCGGCAGCCCACCGCGCUGGCAUCCGCAUCUUUGCCGUGGGCGUGGGCGAGGCACUCAAGGAGGAGCUGGAGGAGAUCGCCUCAGAGCCCAAGUCCGCCCACGUCUUCCACGUGUCCGACUUCAAUGCCAUCGACAAGAUCCGGGGCAAGCUGCGGCGCCGUCUUUGUGAAAAUGUGCUCUGUCCUAGCGUUCGUGUAGAAGGAGAUCGCUUUAAGCACACCAAUGGAGGAACCAAGGAAAUCACAGGUUUUGACCUGAUGGAUUUGUUCAGUGUGAAGGAAAUCUUGGGGAAGAGAGAGAAUGGAGCUCAGAGUUCCUAUGUACGGAUGGGAUCCUUCCCUGUGGUGCAAAGUACUGAGGAUGUGUUCCCCCAAGGUUUACCUGAUGAGUACGCCUUUGUCACAACCUUCCGGUUCAGGAAAACCUCUCGGAAGGAAGACUGGUAUAUCUGGCAGGUCAUCGACCAGUACAGCAUCCCACAGGUCUCCAUCCGGCUGGAUGGUGAAAACAAGGCAGUCGAGUACAACGCUGUGGGUGCCAUGAAAGAUGCUGUCAGGGUGGUCUUCCGAGGUUCUCGGGUCAAUGACCUCUUUGACCGGGACUGGCACAAGAUGGCCCUGAGCAUCCAGGCCCAGAACGUCUCCCUGCACAUUGACUGUGCGCUGGUGCAGACACUACCCAUCGAGGAACGGGAGAACAUUGACAUCCAGGGCAAGACUGUGAUUGGCAAGCGCCUCUACGACAGUGUGCCCAUUGACUUUGACCUACAGCGGAUUGUGAUCUAUUGUGACUCGAGACACGCAGAAUUGGAGACUUGUUGUGAUAUCCCCUCGGGUCCGUGCCAGGUGACCGUGGUGACAGAGCCUCCACCUCCACCCCCACCCCAGCGGCCUCCCACCCCAGGCAGUGAACAGAUUGGGUUUUUGAAGACCAUCAACUGCUCCUGCCCAGCUGGAGAGAAGGGUGAAAUGGGAGUUGCUGGCCCCAUGGGGCUCCCUGGUCCAAAGGGAGACAUAGGAGCCAUUGGGCCGGUUGGCGCUCCUGGACCUAAGGGAGAGAAAGGUGAUGUGGGCAUAGGACCUUUUGGCCAAGGGGAAAAGGGUGAAAAGGGUUCCCUGGGCCUGCCCGGCCCCCCUGGGAGAGACGGCAGCAAAGGCAUGAGAGGGGAGCCAGGAGAGCUGGGAGAGCCGGGGCUGCCGGGUGAGGUCGGCAUGCGGGGGCCCCAAGGACCACCUGGACUCCCCGGACCUCCUGGACGUGUCGGAGCUCCUGGUCUCCAAGGAGAACGAGGUGAAAAGGGAACUCGAGGAGAAAAGGGAGAGCGAGGCCUGGAUGGAUUCCCUGGGAAGCCUGGGGACACAGGACAGCAGGGCAGGCCCGGCCCUUCUGGUGUGGCAGGACCCCAGGGAGAAAAGGGUGACGUGGGACCUGCGGGGCCACCUGGUGUACCAGGCUCAGUGGUGCAGCAAGAGGGCUUGAAAGGGGAACAGGGAGCUCCAGGACCCAGAGGUCACCAAGGCGCCCCCGGUCCUCCAGGAGCUCGGGGUCCAAUAGGCCCAGAAGGCAGGGAUGGACCUCCUGGUUUGCAAGGUCUCCGAGGGAAGAAAGGUGACAUGGGACCACCUGGAAUCCCUGGAUUGCUGGGGCUGCAGGGCCCUCCAGGACCCCCUGGUGUCCCAGGCCCCCCUGGACCGGGAGGUUCUCCGGGUUUGCCUGGAGAGAUCGGCUUCCCGGGAAAGCCUGGACCUCCUGGGCCCACGGGACCCCCUGGAAAGGACGGGCCAAAUGGACCACCAGGUCCGCCAGGAACCAAGGGAGAACCAGGAGAAAGAGGGGAAGAUGGUCUGCCUGGAAAACCAGGCCUUCGGGGAGAAAUUGGGGAGCAGGGCCUGGCAGGCCGACCUGGAGAGAAGGGAGAAGCAGGCCUCCCAGGGGCUCCAGGCUUCCCAGGUGUGAGAGGAGAGAAAGGAGACCAGGGAGAAAAAGGUGAACUGGGACUUCCAGGACUGAAAGGUGACCGAGGUGAAAAGGGUGAAGCUGGUCCUGCAGGCCCUCCCGGGUUACCUGGAACUACAUCCCUGUUCACACCACAUCCACGGAUGCCCGGAGAACAAGGGCCCAAAGGAGAGAAGGGCGAUCCAGGCCUGCCUGGGGAACCGGGACUGCAGGGCCGUCCUGGAGAAUUGGGGCCUCAGGGACCCACUGGACCACCGGGUGCCAAGGGACAGGAAGGUGCACAUGGGGCUCCUGGAGCAGCUGGAAACCCCGGUGCUCCCGGACAUGUCGGUGCCCCCGGUCCCAGUGGCCCUCCAGGAAGUGUGGGUGCUCCCGGCCUCAGAGGCACCCCAGGGAAAGAUGGGGAGCGUGGUGAGAAGGGUGCAGCGGGGGAAGAAGGCAGCCCAGGGCCAGUUGGUCCCAGGGGAGAUCCUGGUGCUCCUGGGCUCCCUGGGCCACCCGGAAAAGGGAAGGAUGGAGAGCCGGGACUCCGUGGAUCACCUGGACUCCCUGGACCCCUAGGAACCAAGGCUGCUUGCGGAAAAGUCAGAGGGUCAGAAAACUGUGCACUGGGAGGGCAAUGUGUUAAGGGGGAUCGAGGAGCUCCUGGGAUCCCUGGUUCUCCUGGCAGCCGUGGUGACCCAGGCAUUGGGGUUGCUGGCCCUCCUGGCCCUUCCGGACCACCAGGAGACAAAGGAUCCCCGGGAUCACGAGGCUUACCUGGAUUCCCUGGCCCCCAGGGCCCAGCCGGCCGGGACGGUGCACCAGGAAAUCCAGGAGAAAGAGGGCCUCCUGGCAAGCCGGGCCUCUCUUCACUACUGUCUCCAGGGGACAUAAAUCUCUUGGCUAAGGAUGUGUGCAAUGACUGCCCUCCUGGCCCCCCAGGCCUCCCUGGUCUACCAGGUUUUAAAGGGGACAAAGGUGUCCCAGGAAAGCCAGGGAGAGAAGGCACAGAAGGGAAAAAGGGAGAGGCUGGGCCUCCAGGCCUACCAGGGCCCCCAGGAAUAGCUGGACCACAGGGAAGUCAAGGAGAACGUGGUGCAGAUGGUGAGGUUGGGCAGAAAGGUGAUCAGGGUCAUCCUGGAGUUCCAGGUUUCAUGGGGCCCCCAGGGAACCCUGGGCCACCAGGGGCAGAUGGAAUUGCAGGAGCUGCUGGACCACCAGGAAUCCAAGGGUCACCUGGGAAAGAAGGCCCUCCUGGCCCCCAAGGCCCAUCUGGAUUACCCGGAAUCCCAGGAGAAGAAGGCAAAGAGGGCAGAGAUGGAAAGCCGGGUCCCCCUGGAGAGCCGGGCAAAGCAGGAGAGCCAGGUCUACCAGGACCAGAGGGUGCCCGAGGCCCACCUGGCUUCAAGGGACACACAGGCGAUUCUGGUGCACCCGGUCCCCGGGGAGAGUCUGGUGCCAUGGGGCUUCCUGGUCAGGAAGGGUUACCAGGAAAAGAUGGUGACACUGGACCCACUGGGCCACAGGGUCCCCAAGGACCAAGGGGCCCACCGGGCAAGAAUGGAUCACCGGGAUCUCCAGGAGAGCCUGGCCCUUCAGGAACCCCUGGCCAGAAAGGAAGCAAAGGGGAAAAUGGCAGCCCAGGACUUCCUGGCUUCCUGGGUCCCCGUGGGCCUCCGGGAGAACCAGGAGAGAAAGGAGUCCCAGGCAAGGAGGGGGUCCCUGGGAAGCCUGGAGAGCCUGGAUUCAAAGGAGAAAGGGGAGAUCCUGGGAUCAAAGGUGACAAAGGACCUCCUGGUGGAAAAGGCCAGCCUGGGGACCCUGGAAUCCCAGGCCACAAAGGCCACACAGGCCUGAUGGGUCCCCAAGGACUACCUGGGGAGAAUGGACCAGUUGGACCCCCAGGGCCUCCAGGCCAGCCGGGAUUUCCAGGACUGAGGGGGGAGUCUCCAUCCAUGGAAACCCUGCGUCGGCUUAUUCAAGAAGAGCUGGGGAAGCAGCUUGAAACCAGACUCGCCUACCUCCUGGCCCAGAUGCCCCCGGCGUACAUGAAGUCAUCUCAAGGCAGACCUGGGCCCCCAGGGCCCCCUGGAAAAGAUGGGCUUCCAGGCCGGGCCGGCCCCAUGGGGGAGCCAGGUCGUCCUGGGCAGGGGGGUCUGGAAGGACCCUCUGGACCCAUAGGUCCCAAAGGUGAGCGAGGAGCCAAAGGUGACCCAGGUGCACCUGGAGUUGGCCUCCGAGGCGAGAUGGGACCCCCUGGAAUCCCAGGUCAACCCGGGGAACCUGGCUAUGCUAAAGAUGGACUUCCUGGGAUCCCUGGCCCUCAAGGGGAGACAGGACCAGCUGGACAUCCUGGCCUCCCAGGACCUCCCGGUCCCCCAGGCCAAUGUGACCCUUCCCAGUGUGCCUACUUCGCCAGCCUUGCUGCCCGGCCGGGUAAUGUGAAGGGUCCCUAAAGGACUCUGGAAAGCCAGAAGACUGCAGUGGAUUUCUGAAACUUGAACUCAGAGCCCAGUGGGAAGCCAGAGGUCUUGAAAGACUUCAGCCAUGUGUUCCUUUUUUUUUUCUUUCUUUUAUCGUUUGCUUUUUGUUUUAUUUUCUUGAGAGACCUCAAAAUUAUUAAAUCCAACAGACGCUGCCGGUCGGUCAGAUUAUUAUUAAUAUUAUUGUUGUUGUUAAUUAUUAUUAUUAUUUCAUAUGCUGAUGCUUUGUGAGUUCUUUUCCACUCCUUUAAAGUUGGGAAAACUUGAUUCGUGGGGCAGGAGAUUGUUUCUUCAUUCUUCUGACAGCCCCCAUCUGACGCGUAACUGCCCAUUUUAAGGAAACUCUUGGUGCUACAAAACCCUGACCAGACACUUGGCAAAUUUACCUCUUUCUUCAAAAGAAAAACUUUAAGAAAAUGAGCCAAUGGGCUUCAUUCUCAGUCAUGCCCGGAGAUCACCCAGGAGAAAUAAUACAAACACCACCACUGUCCAGAGAGAGUAAAGAAGCAGAAAGAGAAAGAAUUUGCAACCAUGAGGAAUGUUCCCACCUCCCGACGGGACGUGCAUUUGGAAAACACAGAAUCAGCCCUCAGGGUGCACUCCAGCCACCUCAGUGCUCUAAGCUCACAGAAGUGAAAUAAUGUCUGUGGGUUGGCAAUGGCUUUGUGGGAUCAUAUGUCUUGGCCAAAGAUGGGAAAACCUAUGUUGAAGAGGCAGCCCUUGAGUGUUAAUUUGUCUUCUAAACUGUGUAAGGCCCCUUCAAGUUCCUCUUGUUGGUUUCAAUUAUAUUAAUUAUAAAACAAGUGGAUGUGGUGACCAUCCACUUGUGUUUCCCUAAUGAUGGGCAGUUGGCCAGGGCACUGACCAGAGCUGGGAAAUUUGUAUCUCCAAGGCGGCUCUGUCUCUGAAAUAAAUGGCAUCAAGUGCAUGUGUGUAUGCGACAUGCCCUGCCUGAACAGGUGCUCAAUAAAUCCAAGUUUCCUUCUCUUGA